CCGGCUGCGCGCGCAGCGGUGGUGGUGGCGGCGCGAUCGGCCGGGCUGUAACCGUCGUCUGUCCGGGAGCGGCUGGAGCGGCAGCGGCGGCCGGGCACGGCGCGAGGUGACGCCACAGGGCAGCGGCGGCAGCGGAGGCAGCGGCGGCAGCAGGAGACGCAGCGGCGGCCGCAGCAGCAGCAGCAAGACGGACUCGUGGAGACGCGCCGCCGCCGCCGCCGCCGGGCCGGGCCGGGUGUCGCGCGCCGAGGCUGGGGGGGAGUCGUCGCCGCCGCCGCCACCGCUACCGCCGCCGCCGCCGCCGCCGAGGUGACUGAGGAGAGAGGCGCCUCCUCGCUCCCGCCACCGCCGGACUUCAAUGCCCAGUCCCCAGCUCGCCAGCGUUUUUCGUUGGAAUAUACGUUGCACAUUUAUGGCGAUUCUGAGUGUGAGGGCAGACUUCUGCCAGGCUCAGCACAGCAUUUUCGCUGACAAGUGAGCUUGGAGGUUCUAUGUGCCAUAAUUAACAUUGCCUUGAAGACUCCUGGACACCGAGACUGGCCUCAGAAAUAGUUGGCUUUUUUUUUUUUUAAUUGCAAGCAUAUUUCUUUUAAUGACUCCAGUAAAAUUAAGCAUCAAGUAAACAAGUGGAAAGUGACCUACACUUUUAACUUGUCUCACUAGUGCCUAAAUGUAGUAAAGGCUGCUUAAGUUUUGUAUGUAGUUGGAUUUUUUGGAGUCCGAAGGUAUCCAUCUGCAGAAAUUGAGGCCCAAAUUGAAUUUGGAUUCAAGUGGAUUCUAAAUACUUUGCUUAUCUUGAAGAGAGAAGCUUCAUAAGGAAUAAACAAGUUGAAUAGAGAAAACACUGAUUGAUAAUAGGCAUUUUAGUGGUCUUUUUAAUGUUUUCUGCUGUGAAACAUUUCAAGAUUUAUUGAUUUUUUUUUUUCACUUUCCCCAUCACACUCACACGCACGCUCACACUUUUUAUUUGCCAUAAUGAACCGUCCAGCCCCUGUGGAGAUCUCCUAUGAGAACAUGCGUUUUCUGAUAACUCACAACCCUACCAAUGCUACUCUCAACAAGUUCACAGAGGAACUUAAGAAGUAUGGAGUGACGACUUUGGUUCGAGUUUGUGAUGCUACAUAUGAUAAAGCUCCAGUUGAAAAAGAAGGAAUCCACGUUCUAGAUUGGCCAUUUGAUGAUGGAGCUCCACCCCCUAAUCAGAUAGUAGAUGAUUGGUUAAACCUGUUAAAAACCAAAUUUCGUGAAGAGCCAGGUUGCUGUGUUGCAGUGCAUUGUGUUGCAGGAUUGGGAAGGGCACCUGUGCUGGUUGCACUUGCUUUGAUUGAAUGUGGAAUGAAGUACGAAGAUGCAGUUCAGUUUAUAAGACAAAAAAGAAGGGGAGCGUUCAAUUCCAAACAGCUGCUUUAUUUGGAGAAAUACCGACCUAAGAUGCGAUUACGCUUCAGAGAUACCAAUGGGCAUUGCUGUGUUCAGUAGAAGGAAAUGUAAACGAAGGCUGACUUGAUUGUGCCAUUUAGAGGGAACUCUUGGUACCUGGAAAUGUGAAUCUGGAAUAUUACCUGUGUCAUCAAAGUAGUGAUGGAUUCAGUACUCCUCAACCACUCUCCUAAUGAUUGGAACAAAAGCAAACAAAAAAGAAAUCUCUCUAUAAAAUGAAUAAAAUGUUUAAGAAAAGAGAAAGAGAAAAGGAAUUAAUUCAGUGAAGGAUGAUUUUGCUCCUAGUUUUGGAGUUUGAAUUUCUGCCAGGAUUGAAUUAUUUUGAAAUCUCCUGUCUUUUUAAACUUUUUCAAAAUAGGUCUCUAAGGAAAACCAGCAGAACAUUAGCCUGUGCAAAACCAUCUGUUUGGGGAGCACACUCUUCCAUUAUGCUUGGCACAUAGAUCUCCCUGUGGUGGGAUUUUUUUUUUCCCUUUUUUUGUGGGGGAGGGUUGGUGGUAUAUUUUUCCCCUCUUUUUUCCUUCCUCUCCUACAUCUCCCUUUUCCCCCGAUCCAAGUUGUAGAUGGAAUAGAAGCCCUUGUUGCUGUAGAUGUGCGUGCAGUCUGGCAGCCUUAAGCCCACCUGGGCACUUUUAGAUAAAAAAAAAAAAAAAACAAAAAACAACACCAAAAAAACAGCAGUGAUAUAUAUAUAUAUAUAUAUAUAUAUAUAUAUAUAUAUAUAUAUAUAUAUAUAUAUAUAUAUAUAUAAUAUAAUAUAUAUAUAUAUAUAUAUAUUUUCCAGGUGGUUUUUAGUCUUUACUGAUGAAAGGGUGUUCAUGUUAGUUUCUUCAAAACCCUAUCUAAUACUAGGCAAAGUAGCCAAGAGCCUUUUGUUUUGUUUUUAUUUUGAUAAAUUAGUGGAGAAAUGGCAUUUUAAGAGGAGUCUCUUCUCAACUUACCUGAGAGUCGAAUUCUUCUCUUCCCUAACCAAUGAAGCUAAGUGGUUAUCCCAGAAACUUGUCUUCUAAAAGGGAGGACUCCAGGCCAUCAAUAAAGAUGUCCAGGCAGUGAGCGUACUUUUUACACCCUGUAGAAUUGUGGGCUGUAGCGUUACUCUGAUUUUCUGUCUAGUAUCAGAGAAUGCUGGUAGCUUAAAAUUUUUAUUUUAGGACUUGUACUCUGAAUUUUCAGGAACCGUCAAAGGAGCAGCAGCAAAUUCACAUAUUUUCGACUUGAGAAAUGCUUGUGGUAUGUGUUUUCCAAACUGCCCCCUAUAUGUAAAGUUCAGUUUAACCACUGAUUGCCUUGUUAUUACUAGGUUUUUUGAGAUUAAAAAAAAAAAAUCCCUGGUUUAAAACCAACAAUGAUGCCUAGUGAGUAUGUGUCCACAGGCCAUAACAGGGUAGAAGAGAGACAUCGUGCAACCCAAUGAGUAGUGAAGGGACUGUGUUGCUUGUGAAGCGGUGUAGUAGCAUUUUUGCAGAUUCUUGGCUGGGUUUAGUGUACUGAUCUAGAAAAGCUGUUUUUCUGCUCCUUUGUGGAAGGCAGUUAUGAUCAGGCUGCAUGGACAAAGCAGGUAGAGGGGCACCAUCAGGGGCUCUUGCACUAUUUUCACCUCUAAAUAUUACGUACUCAGUAGUGCCCUGCUUCUAGGGCUCUGAAUACGGGCUUAAAGUCAUCUUGUCCUGCUGGAAUUUGCUGUGCAGAGCCAUAAGCCUCCCAUUUUGUUAGCGUCAGCUAGGCCAAUAGGAACAGACCGGGACCUUGUCUCACACUGAUGAUACCUCACAUGUUGACCGGCUAUGUGAACUGCCUAUUUCCUAUGCUGGAGUUUUGAUUUUUAACUAAACGCAAAUCUGUAGAUUCUCUCCUCUCCCAUCCCAGAAAACAAAACAAAAUAAUGCUUUUCGAAAUUGUUUCUAGGACUUUAAAACAUAAUGGUAUAUCCAAAAUUCUUUAUUUCAGAAUGCAACAAUAGAUUCCAUUAAUAUAGACUCAAGAUCAAAACAGCAUACCUGCUAAGCUAAGAUAGAUGGUGUUGAUUCCACUGGGUUUUGAUCAAUACAAUAACAAACCUUUUUCCUUUGACAUACUCUGAAUUUUGUUGUUUGGGGGGAGGGGGUGUGUGUGUGUGUGUGUGUGUGUGUGUGUGUAUGUGUGUGUGUGUGUGUGCACGCGCAGUGUCCAUCAGUAUCAGUGCCUGCCUGAGUUAGGAAAAUUACAUUCCUGGUUCUGUAUUGAGGAGAAGGAUGUAUAAAGCAACAUGAAACAUUAGCCCUCCUUUUAUUUUAAAGACUAAUGUUAAUUGUUCUUAAAACUGGAUUUUUUUUCCUUAAAGCAAUUUUUUUCUUUUCGAUUUAAUGAAGUAUUGCUAGCUGAAGCCAGUUUGACAUAGAGAGAUGUCAGAUUGAUUUGAAAGGUGUGCAGCCUGAUUUAAAACCAAACCCUGAACCCUUUUAAAGAACAAUAAAACAUAUUUUACACGCUC